GGUCAGUUGGCAGCGGCAAGCGCGCUGCGGUUCCGGUGGCGCCAUGUCGUUCUGCAGCUUCUUCGGGGGCGAGGUUUUCCAGAAUCACUUUGAACCUGGCGUUUACGUGUGUGCCAAGUGUGGCUAUGAGCUGUUCUCCAGCCGCUCGAAGUAUGCACACUCGUCUCCAUGGCCGGCGUUCACCGAGACCAUUCACGCCGACAGCGUGGCCAAGCGUCCGGAGCACAAUAGAUCUGAAGCCUUGAAGGUGUCCUGUGGCAAGUGUGGCAAUGGGUUGGGCCACGAGUUCCUGAACGACGGCCCCAAGCCGGGGCAGUCCCGAUUCUGAAUAUUCAGCAGCUCGCUGAAGUUUGUCCCUAAAGGCAAAGAAACUUCUGCCUCCCAGGGUCACUAGGCGGGCAGCCCACACCCACCCCAGACGGCCACCACACUGAGGCCACACGUUGGCCAUUCCACCUUGGAGUUGGAACCCUGGGCGUCGAGACAGGAAGGCAGGGCGCAGUGGUUGAAACAUCAGGACACUCCCAAGGCCCCGGCUCUGAACAAGACCUUUUCGUUUCUUGGAAAAGAGACUCAUUUGCUGAUGGUUCAUGCCUUCUGCUGGGACAGGCCUGGGCUGUGCAGCCACACUGUCGGCUGACUUAGCCCCCUGCUCACUCUAGGUGCCUCCAGGAGGUGAGCCCUGGGUGCAGCUGGUCUCUGAAUGACGUUACACCCUCACCUUCUUUUCCUGGCCCUGUCUCUGGACUCUCCCCUGUGAGGCCCAAUUCCAAGACAGACUCUCGUCCUCACCGAAGCUUAGGCCCACAUCUCCCAGGCUGCUUAGGAGACAGAAUGGAAACGGAGGCCGCCCCUGCCAGCCGCCCUGGCCCUGGUCACUGCAUGAUCCGCUCUGGUCAAACCCUUCCAGGCCAGCCAGAGUGGGGAUGGUCUGUGACCUGCUGGGAAGGCAGGCUGAUGGGGCACACCCUUGGCCUCUCGUCCACGAGGGGAGAAACCUAAACCCUGUUUCACAAUCUGUGCGGAAGUAGCUUGCCUCACUUCUGCUUAGGAAAGCGGCUGUUGCUCCAUAACUCUAACCAGCACAGGGCUGAGGCCUGCAGUGCACACCUGCAGGGAGGCCCUUCCCAAGGUGUGGUGACUGUGCCUUACUGUACAUGCUCGGAGGCCUGGCCAUAUAGGAGGGUGGGUGAUGCUGAAAUCACCCCCCAUCUUAAGUAAUUACUUUCUGGAGUAAUCAGGUGGAAAUCCAUAGACAAAUGAAACAUUCAGAUGUA